AGUCGCGUCUUUCUCACUCACUGGGGAGCCCGGCGGUGGCGGCACCUUUCGAGGUAGACCCGCUGAGCUGCUAGCCCGCCGGCCAGCGAGUGAGAGGUCGGACAGACUGUGGAGCCGACAGACUGAAGGACAGCGGCACCGCCAGACGGCCAGAAAGUUCCGCCAUGAGCUGGGGCACGGAGCUGUGGGAUCAGUUCGACAGCUUAGACAAGCAUACACAAUGGGGAAUUGACUUCUUGGAAAGAUAUGCCAAAUUUGUUAAAGAGAGGAUAGAAAUUGAACAGAACUAUGCGAAACAAUUGAGAAAUCUGGUUAAGAAGUACUGCCCCAAACGUUCAUCCAAAGAUGAAGAGCCACGGUUUACCUCGUGUGUAGCCUUUUUUAAUAUCCUUAAUGAGUUAAAUGACUAUGCAGGACAGCGAGAAGUUGUAGCAGAAGAAAUGGCGCACAGAGUGUAUGGUGAAUUAAUGAGAUAUGCUCAUGAUCUGAAAACUGAAAGAAAAAUGCAUCUGCAAGAAGGACGAAAAGCUCAACAAUAUCUUGACAUGUGCUGGAAACAGAUGGAUAAUAGUAAAAAGAAGUUUGAAAGAGAAUGUAGAGAGGCAGAAAAGGCACAACAGAGUUAUGAAAGAUUGGAUAAUGAUACUAAUGCAACCAAGGCAGAUGUUGAAAAGGCCAAACAGCAGUUGAAUCUGCGUACGCAUAUGGCCGAUGAAAAUAAAAAUGAAUAUGCUGCACAAUUACAAAACUUUAAUGGAGAACAACAUAAACAUUUUUAUGUAGUGAUUCCUCAGAUUUACAAGCAACUACAAGAAAUGGACGAACGAAGGACUAUUAAACUCAGUGAGUGUUACAGAGGAUUUGCUGACUCAGAACGCAAAGUUAUUCCCAUCAUUUCAAAAUGUUUGGAAGGAAUGAUUCUUGCAGCAAAAUCAGUUGAUGAAAGAAGAGACUCUCAAAUGGUGGUAGACUCCUUCAAAUCUGGUUUUGAACCUCCAGGAGACUUUCCAUUUGAAGAUUACAGUCAACAUAUAUAUAGAACCAUUUCUGAUGGGACUAUCAGUGCAUCCAAACAGGAGAGUGGGAAGAUGGAUGCCAAAACCACAGUAGGAAAGGCCAAGGGCAAAUUGUGGCUCUUUGGAAAGAAGCCAAAGGGCCCAGCACUAGAAGAUUUCAGUCAUCUGCCACCAGAACAGAGACGUAAAAAACUACAGCAGCGCAUUGAUGAACUUAACAGAGAACUACAGAAAGAAUCAGACCAAAAAGAUGCACUCAACAAAAUGAAAGAUGUAUAUGAGAAGAAUCCACAAAUGGGGGAUCCAGGGAGUUUGCAGCCUAAAUUAGCAGAGACCAUGAAUAACAUUGACCGCCUACGAAUGGAAAUCCAUAAGAAUGAGGCUUGGCUCUCUGAAGUCGAAGGCAAAACAGGUGGGAGAGGAGACAGAAGACAUAGCAGUGACAUAAAUCAUCUUGUAACACAGGGACGAGAAAGUCCUGAGGGAAGUUACACUGAUGAUGCAAACCAGGAAGUCCGUGGGCCACCCCAGCAGCAUGGUCACCACAAUGAGUUUGAUGAUGAAUUUGAGGAUGAUGAUCCCUUGCCUGCUAUUGGACACUGCAAAGCUAUCUACCCUUUUGAUGGACAUAAUGAAGGUACUCUAGCAAUGAAAGAAGGUGAAGUUCUCUACAUUAUAGAGGAGGACAAAGGUGACGGAUGGACAAGAGCUCGGAGACAGAACGGUGAAGAAGGCUACGUUCCCACGUCAUACAUAGAUGUAACUCUAGAGAAAAACAGUAAAGGUGCAGUAACUUAUAUCUAAACUAACCAGGCACCUUUGUGCCAUGUGUGACAUAGGAAGAGUAACAUAAAAUGAAAACACAUUCAACAGGUUGAAAAAAAUAAGGAAACUUAAAGGGCAUCCAAGAUUAAUUGUUCACUAUGUGAGCUGAGUGUAGGCUUGAUCUUGUGAAUAUUACCACAAGAAACAUUUUGUGGCACUUUACUGUUUGAGUAACGUUGGUGUGAAGCUUAAUUGAUGCCUUUUGCUUUAUGUCCCGCUUAAGUCUGUGUGAAGGAUUUGUGUUUUUCUGCCUUACAAAUAGAAUUUGAUUUAUUGGGCAGGAAUUCAUGGAUAGUAAUGCUCUCUGCCCCCUUUACUUCAGAAAACACAGUGACUUUAGUGAAUUUGAAUAGUGAAACUGCUCUGAAAUGCUAUGGAAAGCCGACUCCCCAAAGAGUGGUUUCUUCUAGAAGUUUGAAUUUGUAGCUACAGUUUCCAAGAAGAAAAAUAGUAGUUGGAUAAUUUAGUAAAAUAAUAACAUCAUUUUCAUUUUCUUACCUAUUCUUAACUUUGGUUUCCUAAAGGAAGAAAAUGAGCAGGUAGCACAUAAUCUAUUUAAGUAGAUUUAAAGAGAGUUUCAAAAUAAAUCUCCUGGUCUAGCUCUUAGGUGAAUAAAAUAGAUUUUGUUUGAGACCUCAAAAUAUUUUGAGGUUAGCUGGUAAUUUUCAAUAAUUUACAAGCUUCCUUCCAAACUAAUCUCAUACUUUUGUAUGUUUCAUCUUGAAAAUAUCUUUUGGGAAAUACCACUUUAGUGAUUAUUUAGCAUUUAGCAGUUACACAUAGGAAAAUACACAGUUACAUAGAAAAAUACACAUUUGAAGAUAGAGGAAACCUUGAAUGGAGGGGAAGUGUUGACAAAUUUUAAUUUUUAAAGGAGAAACUUUUUGACUAUCUGGGUUAGAGGAAGAUAUGUGUACCGCCUUUAGGGCAUUUUGUUAUUUCCGCUGAAUCAUUAGUUAUUAGGAUAGAUAAAUUUUUCCAAUUAGUUUCAGCAAGCGUUGUUGGAAACACUGUGCAGUCAAGGAUUGUGCAGUGCUGGUUGUGUGACCACACCCUGAGUCAGUGGUGUGGGGAAGUAAAGUGUGAAGAAGCAGUAAGAUUGGUUUUUAAUUUUGCCCAUGUUUUAAAUUUUCCUGGUGUUUUCGGUAGCUGACUAUAAAAUGAUAGAGACAUUUGGGACAGGCACUUUAAACUGAACACCCCUUUUGGUUUUACCAAAGGUCUUCAGUAAUUGUUCUUUUCUUUUUCCUCCUGGACUGCAGGUUCCUGAAGAGGGUUUCUGAGGAAAUGGGCAAGAUGUUGAAGGAGGUUACAUGCAGCUGCUUUUGGGGGAGGGUAUUAGAGUUGUCAGGCUCAAAGAGAGUGAGAGAAGCAAGUUGCAUGAGUGCAUGCAGACAUGAUUUUUUUUUUACUAACUUCAUUAGCAUUUCCAUACAUUGUUUUUAAAAAUCAUAAUACCAACCCUUAAGUUCCUAGUUCACAGUUAUUCCCACAAAAGAAAAAGCCAACAAUAGUGUACCAUUUUUCUAUUUAUUUUAUUGCUGUCUAAUCAAUAAAGAAUGCAGAGCUGUCAAAAAAUGUGUCUUACAUUAGCUGUCCCAACAGGAUUGUCUUCCCUCCCAGCUCUGUUUUAAUUGGCUUUUAGACCCACUAUCUGUCAGAUCCUUGCCAUCUGUCAGUGUCUGCCUGCGCCACCUCCGUGCUUGCUUAACAUCCUGUUGCAUGUCUAGCGUGAUUGAGCUAGAUUUUUCAGGCAUGUCUUUAGAUUCCCUUGUUCUUGUCAAAGCCUUGUUUUGUUUUACAUUUGUAGUGCAAAUCACUUUGUCAAACAUCUCCAGCACUAAUGUUUCCAUCUUAGUAUUUGUGCACACUGCUAUAACUUCCCCACUGCAAACAUUCCAGUUUUGGCAUUACGAAGAAGUAGCUGUGAACCUGAAGUAUUUAUGAUAAGAAAAAGAAAACAUCUCUGCUGUAGCCUACAGCCCAGUUGAAAGAACUCUUUGAAACGUGAUACAUCUUCAGCACCUCAGUCUGGGAAGAAUCUAGUCAGCACUGAAAUCCUGGCAUAAUAAACACAGAAGAUAUUCACCACCUCAAGACAAAGGACUAUUGUCAAAAGUCAGCUGCUUCCAUUCAAAUGCUGCCUUAAACUUGAGUGCCUAAAUCUGUUGAUUGCCAACACUACCACUACAGUAUCCCACAAAGGGCUUUAUGUGUCAGCUCAGUGCGACCUGCUUUAACUCUGCAGCACCGCUGCAGCUGCCGAUGUAGCCUCGGUAGGUGGCUAUUAGAGCUCUACCAUAUACAGUGGUGCAUCUUCAAAUUUAUGCAUCAAACUAAAGACAUGUCCAAGUCCAUUUUAAUUUCCUCAGUGGUUUUAUGAGAAGUUUUAUGGGCCUCCCCCAAUUGUCUUUUUAUUUUGGGUUAUGACGAUCAUGUUUGAUAAUUACAAUGAUAGUCUCUUUCCACGUGAUGCUUUUGUUUGAACCUGAUAAAAUUUAGUGAAACUUUGUAAUGAUCUAUGUGCACUUUUACUUGUAAAAUGGAAUUUCUGUAUGUUUAUACUUGUAAAUAUGAUUGUUGUUAGUGCUCCUGUUGCUCAUGGUGUCCUGCCUCGCAUUUGUGAUUCUGUUAAUGACAUGUAUCUUAACUAAUUUCUUAGUGGUGUUGUAAUAGGGAGAUGGGGCAGGUGGGGGGUUAUUUGUACCACUGAAUCUUCAUUAAUUUGGUUCUUUACUGUUUUGAGGGGAGAAAGAACGUGAAAUGGUUUGUGUAUUAUUGAAUUUUAAGCAAUAUUUUAGAAGCUGUGUGACUGCUUUAAUAACUUUUUCCCAGUGUUAUUUGAAUCAUACUACCCGUUAUACUAAAGCUGAAUGACAAUUGUGUGAAAGUUACUGCCUUCAUAAGAUCAAGUCACCACUGUUACACAGCUGACAUAUAGUGUAUUACCUUUGCAGCUAGUAAACUAUAAAGUUUAGAUAUUGAAUCUCGUUACAGGGUUAUUUAUAUAAUGUGACAUUAUUCAGUACUGACAGACUACAUGAAGUAGUUUUAAAAUCUAGUGCUAUUUUUAUUUUAAAGGUUAGCAAUGAGGAGGAAAUGUGAUCUGGCUGUGUUUGUCUUCUGUACAAAGCCUGAAGUGCUUAUGGUUUUUUGGCUAACAGCCACAGAGGGCAAAGUUUAAGACUUUCUUGUAAGGACUAACUGUUCUUUUCAAGCUACUGUUUGUUUUUCUAAAAGCAGGAUUUGCUUCCGUAGGAGGCAAGUUCCUUGAUGUGGAAUAGUGCAACCUGUAUAUGGGUUAUUAUAAUAGGAAAGACAUUUGUACUUGCACAGUUUAAAUCAUUCUUAAAUUUUGAACAUGUGAAUUGUCCCAAAAAAUCUUUAAUUUUUUGGUAAUUUUUACUCUUUUUGUGCACAUGUUGAUUUCUUAAUGGUAAAUCCUUCAUUUAAAGAUAGUGUUCUCUGUUGAGAAUAUUUACAUGGAAUAAAACAAUCUUUUCAUGGCCUGUUAA